ACAGACGCUGGCGGCCACCAGAAGUUUGAGCCUCUUUGGUAGCAGGAGGCUGGAAGAAAGGACAGAAGUAGCUCUGGCUGUGAUGGGGAUCUUACUGGGCCUGCUACUCCUGGGGCACCUAACAGUGGACACUUAUGGCCGUCCCAUCCUGGAAGUGCCAGAGAGUGUAACAGGACCUUGGAAAGGGGAUGUGAAUCUUCCCUGCACCUAUGACCCCCUGCAAGGCUACACCCAAGUCUUGGUGAAGUGGCUGGUACAACGUGGCUCAGACCCUGUCACCAUCUUUCUACGUGACUCUUCUGGAGACCAUAUCCAGCAGGCAAAGUACCAGGGCCGCCUGCAUGUGAGCCACAAGGUUCCAGGAGAUGUAUCCCUCCAAUUGAGCACCCUGGAGAUGGAUGACCGGAGCCACUACACGUGUGAAGUCACCUGGCAGACUCCUGAUGGCAACCAAGUCGUGAGAGAUAAGAUUACUGAGCUCCGUGUCCAGAAACUCUCUGUCUCCAAGCCCACAGUGACAACUGGCAGCGGUUAUGGCUUCACGGUGCCCCAGGGAAUGAGGAUUAGCCUUCAAUGCCAGGCUCGGGGUUCUCCUCCCAUCAGUUAUAUUUGGUAUAAGCAACAGACUAAUAACCAGGAACCCAUCAAAGUAGCAACCCUAAGUACCUUACUCUUCAAGCCUGCGGUGAUAGCCGACUCAGGCUCCUAUUUCUGCACUGCCAAGGGCCAGGUUGGCUCUGAGCAGCACAGCGACAUUGUGAAGUUUGUGGUCAAAGACUCCUCAAAGCUACUCAAGACCAAGACUGAGGCACCUACAACCAUGACAUACCCCUUGAAAGCAACAUCUACAGUGAAGCAGUCCUGGGACUGGACCACUGACAUGGAUGGCUACCUUGGAGAGACCAGUGCUGGGCCAGGAAAGAGCCUGCCUGUCUUUGCCAUCAUCCUCAUCAUCUCCUUGUGCUGUAUGGUGGUUUUUACCAUGGCCUAUAUCAUGCUCUGUCGGAAGACAUCCCAACAAGAGCAUGUCUACGAAGCAGCCAGGUAAGAAAGUCUCUCCUCUUCCAUUUUUGACCCCGUCCCUGCCCUCAAUUUUGAUUACUGGCAGGAAAUGUGGAGGAAGGGGGGUGUGGCACAGACCCAAUCCUAAGGCCGGAGGCCUUCAGGGUCAGGACAUAGCUGCCUUCCCUCUCUCAGGCACCUUCUGAGGUUGUUUUGGCCCUCUGAACACAAAGGAUAAUUUAGAUCCAUCUGCCUUCUGCUUCCAGAAUCCCUGGGUGGUAGGAUCCUGAUAAUUAAUUGGCAAGAAUUGAGGCAGAAGGGUGGGAAACCAGGACCACAGCCCCAAGUCCCUUCUUAUGGGUGGUGGGCUCUUGGGCCAUAGGGCACAUGCCAGAGAGGCCAACGACUCUGGAGAAACCAUGAGGGUGGCCAUCUUCGCAAGUGGCUGCUCCAGUGAUGAGCCAACUUCCCAGAAUCUGGGCAACAACUACUCUGAUGAGCCCUGCAUAGGACAGGAGUACCAGAUCAUCGCCCAGAUCAAUGGCAACUACGCCCGCCUGCUGGACACAGUUCCUCUGGAUUAUGAGUUUCUGGCCACUGAGGGCAAAAGUGUCUGUUAAAAAUGCCCCAUUAGGCCAGGAUCUGCUGACAUAAUUGCCUAGUCAGUCCUUGCCUUCUGCAUGGCCUUCUUCCCUGCUACCUCUCUUCCUGGAUAGCCCAAAGUGUCCGCCUACCAACACUGGAGCCGCUGGGAGUCACUGGCUUUGCCCUGGAAUUUGCCAGAUGCAUCUCAAGUAAGCCAGCUGCUGGAUUUGGCUCUGGGCCCUUCUAGUAUCUCUGCCGGGGGCUUCUGGUACUCCUCUCUAAAUACCAGAGGGAAGAUGCCCAUAGCACUAGGACUUGGUCAUCAUGCCUACAGACACUAUUCAACUUUGGCAUCUUGCCACCAGAAGACCCGAGGGAGGCUCAGCUCUGCCAGCUCAGAGGACCAGCUAUAUCCAGGAUCAUUUCUCUUUCUUCAGGGCCAGACAGCUUUUAAUUGAAAUUGUUAUUUCACAGGCCAGGGUUCAGUUCUGCUCCUCCACUAUAAGUCUAAUGUUCUGACUCUCUCCUGGUGCUCAAUAAAUAUCUAAUCAUAACAGCAA